AGUUCCUACCAGAGCCGCUGCGGGUGCCAUUCCACCCAUGGCCGGACACAGGCCCUCAAACCACUUCUGCCCCCUUCCAGGCAGUGGUGGGGGCGGCCCCAGAGGGCCGAUGCCCCUGCGGGUUGACACUCUGACCUGGUUGAGCACCCAGGCGGCCCCUGGCAGGGUGAUGGUCUGGCCGGCAGUCAGGCCAGGGAUCUGCCCAGGCCCUGACGUGUGGAGGAUUCCCCUGGGUCCCCUGCCACACGAAUUCCGGGGCUGGAUAGCACCCUGCAGGCCCCGUCUUGGAGCUAGUGAGGCAGGGGACUGGUUGCGACGCCCCUCCGAAGGCGCCCUCCCGGGGCCCUACAUUGCCCUGCGGAGCAUUCCGAAGUUGCCGCCGCCAGAGGACAUCUCGGGCAUACUGAAAGAGUUGCAGCAAUUGGCCAAGGAGUUGAGGCAGAAGAGGUUGAGCCUAGGGUACUCGCAGGCCGAUGUGGGGAUCGCUGUGGGAGCUCUGUUUGGGAAGGUGCUUAGCCAGACGACCAUCUGCCGCUUCGAGGCCCAGCAGCUAAGCGUCGCCAACAUGUGGAAGCUGCGACCACUGCUGAAAAAGUGGCUGAAGGAAGUGGAAGCAGAGAACCUUCUGGGCUUAUGCAAAAUGGAGAUGAUCCUGCAACAGUCUGGGAAGUGGAGACGGGCAAGCAGAGAGCGACGAAUCGGAAACAGCCUGGAGAAAUUCUUCCAGCGGUGCCCUAAGCCCACACCCCAGCAAAUCAGCCACAUUGCUGGGUGCCUCCAGCUGCAGAAGGAUGUGGUUCGAGUUUGGUUCUAUAACCGCAGCAAGAUGGGCAGUCGACCAACCAAUGAUGCUUCCCCACGGGAGAUUGUGGGGACAGCCGGGCCUCCUUGCCCAGGAGCACCAGUGUGCUUUCACCUGGGACUGGGGCUCCCAGUGGAUAUCCCCCACUAUACACGUCUCUACUCUGCAGGGGUAGCCCACUCCUCUGCCCCAGCCACCACUCUGGGCCUCCUCAGAUUUUAGGGCUGAGGGGCUUGCCCUUCACGGCACGGUUGGAGAGGGGAGAAGAAGGGAAAACCCAGGAAAUGUCCCUAGGGUUCAUUUGAGGGCUUUUAGUAUUAAUUUCUCAUUCACUGUCUAAAGAAGUUAAGGAUACAUAGUAGGGAAUGGGGGUGGGAAUUGUUCAAGAAAAACCUGGGAGAGAAGAUGAAGUUUAUUGCAGUUUUGUGUUUUCCCUUUGUUUUUCCCUAGCAUUGGUUUAAAGGUACAUUACAGUAUAUAGAUGGUUUCGAUAUUUUGUUCCUUUUUUUAUUAAAUAUUGUGUCUGUUAUUCCUUGUGGUUAUCAGUAAACAUAGGGUUUAAAUUUUUUCAUAAACACAAUACUAAGUGAAAAACUCAAGUCACAGAAGACUACCUUAGUAUACAAUUUUUUACUUAAAAUCAAGCAGAACUCUGUGUAAACACAAACACAAAAUCCAGGAUAAUAGUUAUCUUGAGGGAAUGACUUGAGAAUGUGAUAGGGAAGAAACACACAGAGCCCACCUAGAGCCCUUGCUGAAACACCUGAGCUUUCUUGGAAGAUUUUUUUUUUUUUUUUUUUUUCUGAUUUACCUUUUCAUUUCUGGUGCCCCAGCUUCAUGUCAGGGUCUCAGUUCCUCUCCCUACUUUAUGUAGUCCCAUGGGACUAUGUCUUGUCCUGCCACAGUCACUGUAUUCUAAACUCCUUUGUUACUGAGGUUGGCAAGCUGGACUUCAGAGCUUCGGUCCCAGCUGUAGCUUACUCCUCCUGUUUUCACCUCUAUUUGGUUCCCUGGGAAUUUCCCUUACUUUCUCUUGAUCUCUUAUAAUGGUUUUGAGAGGAUAUUUGUAAUAGUUUAUCCAAACUUCCCUGGUGGUUUUUGCCAUUAAACGUCAAAUAACUCUUCUAAUUUCAUCUCUGAAAUUGGUCUUUUCAGUUUUCCACUUCUACUUUGGUCAAUUUUGGUCACCAUAUACUAAAUGGAAACCAUUUAGUACCUCUGUGUUUUCAAAUCUGCUGUCACACACCUGCAUGCUCUAUUUAUUGUCCUAGAAUUCUAUCAGUAUGUAUUAUAUCAGAGUUUAUGUCUUAUUUCUGGAUAGUAAUCUUGUCAAUGUUUGCUUUUUUUGUGAUCAGUCUUGCAAAUGUUUUAUCUAUAGGUAUUUUCAAAGUAUAAGCUUUUUUACUUAUUCUACUUACUACAAUUUUUAUUCCCUAGUUAAUUAAUUUUUACUUCAUUCUUCUUAAUUUUUUCCUAGUUUCUUCUGGUUUCUUUCAUUGUUCUUUUUUAGAUAAUUUUUAGAUGAGUACUUAGUUUCUUUCUUUCUUUCUUUUUUUUUCUGGUGGCUGUAUAGAGAAUAACUCUUGUGGGCCCAAGAGUGCAAACCAGGAGCCCAAUAAGAGACUUAACUCUGGGCCGGGCAUGGUGGCUCAUGCCUGUAAUCCCAGCACUUUGGGAGACCAAGGCAGGCAGAUCACAAGGUCAAGAGAUCGAGAGUUAACUCUGAUCUUCUGACCUCAAGUCCAGGGAUAAUUUUACUGUCACACAAGUCAGGUGUGACUAAGCUUUUUAUUUAAUCUUUUCUUCAUGAGACUGUAGAAACUUUACCUUUGCCUAUUUUUGUGUGUGUGAUAAAAUAUAAAAUUUGCCAUUGUAAUGAUUUUAAGUGUAAAUUCAGUGACAUUAAUUACAUUCACAAUGUUAGGCAACCAUCACCACUAUCCAUUUCCAACAUUUUUCCAUCACUCCAAACAUAAACUCUUCUCAUUAAGCAAUAACUCCAUUCCCCUAUCCCCUACCCCUGGUAACCUUUCUGUGAAUUUGCCAGUUCUAAGCAGUUCAUAUUCAUGGAACCAUACAACAUUUGACCUUUUGUAUCUGGCUUAUUUCACUUAGCACAUUUUCAAGGUUCAUCUGUGUUGUAGUGUGUAUCAGAACUUCAUUCCUUUUUUAUGACUGAAUAAUAUUCCAUUGUAUGGAUAUAUACCACAUUUUGUUUAUCCAUUCCUCUGAUGAUGGGCACUUAGAUUGUUUUCAUUAAUAGCCAAUGGGCUAUUGUGAAUGAUACUGCUAUGAACAUUUACAUAUAAUAAUCUAUUUGUUUAUCUGUUGUUUCAGUUCUCUUGGAUGUAUACAUAGGAGUGGAAUUUCUGAGUCAUACAGUAAUUCUAUGCUUAACUUUUUGGGAAACUACCAAACUGUUUUCCAUAGUGAAGGCACCAUUUUACAUUCCCACCAGCAAUCUACAAGAGUUCUAGUUUUUCCAUAUCCCUGGCAACACUUGUUAUUUUUUAAAAAAUUAUAGCCAUCUUGGUAGCUGUUAAGUGGUGUCUCAUUGUGGUUUUGAUUUGUAUUUCUCUAAUGACUAAUGAUGUUGAGCAUCUUUUCAUAUGCUUAUUGUCUAUUUUGUAUCUUCUUUAAAGAAAUGUCUAUUCAAGUCCUUUGCCUAUUUUUAAAACUGGGUUGUUUGUCUUUUCUUCAUAGAGUCUGGAUAUUAAGCCCUUAUCAGAUAGAUGGUUUGCAAGUAUUUUCUCCCAUUCUGUGGGUUGUCCUUUUACUCUUUUGACUGUAUCUUUUGAUGCAGACAGACUUUAAUUUUUAUUAAGUCCAGCUUAUCCAUUUUUUCUUUUGUUGCUUAGGCUUUUCAUGUUGCCAAAUGCAAAGUCAUGAAGAUUUGCUCCUGUGUUUUCUUCUAUGAAUUUUACAGUUUUAUUUAUUAAAUUUAGGACUUUGAUCCAUUUCAAGUUAAUUUUUGUAUACGGUAUGAGGUAAGUGCCCAACUUCAUUCUUUUGCAUGUGGAUAGCCAGUUUUCCCAGCACCAUUUGUUGAGGAGAUGUUCUUUCUGCAUUGAAUGAUCUUAGCACCCUUGUCAAAAAUCAGUUGACCACACAUGUGAGGGAUUAUUUCUGGGCUCUCAACUCUCUUCUGUUGGUCUAUAUGUCUGUCUUUAUGCCAGUACCACACUGUUUUGACUACUGUAGCUUUGCAGUAAGUUUUGAAAUGGGGAAGUGUGAGUCUUCCAAUUUUGUUCUUCCAUAUAUAUAUAUAUGGCACGUAUAUAUAUAUGGCAUAUAUAUACAUGCCAUAUGUAUAUAUACACACACACACCAUUGUGGGUUACUUGAAAUUUCAUAGGAAUUUUAGGAUCAGUUUUUCCAUUUCUGCCCAAAACACCAUUGAGAUUUUGUUACAGAGUGCAUUGAACCCUCAUAUUGCUUUAGGGAGUGUUGUCAUCUUAGCAAUUUUAAGUCUUCCAAUCCAUGAACACAGGCUGUCUUUCCACUUAUGUCUUCUUUAAUUUCUUUGAGCAGUGUUUUAGUUUUCAGUGUACAAGCCUUUCACUUUCUUAAAGUUAUUUGUGGGCAUUUUAUUCUUUUGGAUACUACUGUAAAUGGAAUAGUUUCCUUCAUUUCCUUUUGAAAUUGUUCAUCGCUAAUGGAUAGAAAUACAACUGAUUUUCCUGUGUUGAUUUUGUAUCCUGCGACUUAUGCAGAUUUAGUUCUAACCAGUUUUUUGGUGCAUUCUUUAGGGUUUUCUACAUAUAAAUCAUAUCAUCUGUGAAUAAAGAUAGUUUUGCUUCUUCCUUUCCGAUUUGGAUACCCUUUCUUUUUCUUACUCACUUGCUCUGGCAAAAAUGUGUAGUACUGUGUUGUAUAAAAGUAGCAGAAGAGGACAUCCUUGUCUUGUUUUUGUUCUUAGGAGAAAAACUUUUAGUCUUUUCACCAUUGAGUAUGACAUUAGCUCUGGCUUUUUCAUACGUACUCUACAUGUUGAGGAAGUUCCUUUUUUCUUAGGUUAUUGAAUGUUUUAUAUGCGAGGGUAUGGGUUUUUGACAGUUUCUCUGGAAUAAAUGAAAAAUGCUUAAGGGAAAUAUGAAAUCCUAUGACUAUUUCAUAAGAUUAUGCUAACUACCAGUACCACUACUUCCUUCCCCAGUACUACCAUCACCAUUGCACCCACACCUAAGAGACCUAAACUUUUUUUUUCCUCCGACUCUAAGGGUGGUUAUUUUUCUGUUUUGAGGGAUCUCAUUCUCAUGACAUCUUUGUGUAAGAGUAAAUGACUCACCCGGGGUGAUGAAAAUAAGUUUUAAACCAGAUCUUCCAUAGUCCACAACAUGAAGUAGCCCAGAUGUAGCUCAGCUUUCAGGAAUGAACUUUUGGUGAAGUACUUUAAAAACAAAAGUCAAGUAAAUAUUAAUGCUGCACUUACAUUCUUCUAACUCUUUAAAAAGAUUACUUAAUUAUAAACAAAUUGUAACAACUUUAGUUUUCAGAACACACCUAUAAGCUGUAUUGUUUCAGGUGGACAAUGGAGGUGUAUCAAGAUUACACAUAUACACUUGUAUAAGAUUAGCUUGAGUUCCCAGUUUAUUUACUCAAGAAUAUAGAAUCACAUUGGAAAUAUGAUGGCCACAAAGCAAGUGUAAAUGAACCGUAUAUAUCAGCACAGCUUCCCAUGGUCCAGCGUCCUUGAUGACAAUGCCCAAAAUACGGCACUGGAUAAAAAGUGUGGAAAUGAAUUCCACACUACAGCUUUUUUAUCCUUAGGGCUACAUCAGUGCUCAAGAAAAACUUAAUGUCUGCUCUUAAUGCUUCCAUUUAAGAGAAUGUUUGGAGAUAUUAAGCUUCUUCUGGUUCUUGGACCAAACUCACUACAGUGAAUCCACAACAUCAUCAAGCAGAAGAAUCUGAAUUAGUGCCUGGGUCUCUGAUCCCAGCUUACAACAUCACAGUGAGACCAUUUCCUCCACACAAGCUACAGGGACCCAGCUUAACAAAUGUAUGCUUUUUCUUCUUGUCAGUGUCUAAAGGUAGAGCACUGAGGAUCCACAUAAGUUAGUGAAAAUAAAGCCAAAUCCUAAUUGCUUAGCUUUAGAUUCUAUAGGUGACUAAUCACUUGCUGUUGGAUUAUCCCAUUAAAAGUCACACAGCACCAACUCCAUUUCCUCCUUUUCCUAGACAGCCCUUCUGGAAAGCCUUAGAAAGGAGAUGUUUCAGCAGAGUCAGACCAUGUUGAAUGCCAGAAUAAACAACUCUGAUUGUGUUGUGAACAUAAGAGCUGUAAAGAGGCACUGACCUCAGCUGCUCCUUCAGUUCUUCUGCAGCCUCUACAGAUGUGGAGAAAUUGUGAUGAGCUCUCAAUCUCAGGGAACAGCUCCUAGAGUCCAUCUCAGCCCCCGCAUAGCUGCAUCAUUGACACAGCUGCCCCACCUCUGCUUAGGCAAAGCCUCUAUGUGUCACUAAUCAGCUUCACAUAAUUUAAAAGAUUUUCUAUCACUAGAUCUCUUGACUUGCUGUGAAAAGAGAAAAGGCUGGACCUUAGGGAAAACUUCAUACUGAAGUGAUUUCAGAUUUUUCAGAGAUUUAAGAUGAUAUGUAGAAACUUUAAUCAGAAGAUCCCUUAAACAGAAGAAUAACUACCCUUAGAGUUGGGAGAAAACCAAGACUAUAUUGUUAAGUAGUUAACAAUGUUAAAUGUUACAGAGAUCAAGUAACAUAAGAAAUCAACCAAGAUACAUUGGCCAGGUGCGGUGGCUCAUGCCUGUAAUUCCAGCACUUUGGGAGGCCGAGGUGGACAGAUCACUUGAGGUCAGGAGUUCGAGACCAGCCUGGCCAACAUGGUGAAACCCCGUCUCUACUAAAAGUACAAAAAUUAGCCGGGCAUGGUGGUGUGCACCUUAAUCCCAGCUACUCAGGAGGCUGAGGCAGUAGAAUCGCAGCCUGGGCAACAAAGUGAGACUCUGUCUCAAAAAAAAAAAGCAAAAGAAAAAGAAAUCUACUAAGCCAUAUCAUUUCAAUAACUAAGAUGCCAUUGAUACCUUUAGUAAUAAUUUCAGUGGCAUAAUUAGUAAAGGCAGAUGUCAAACACUCCAAAGUCUUCAUAUUUGCCCAGAUUUUCCCCUGCCUUAAUUUUAAAAAUAAAUUUCAACUCCCGACUCCAAUAGAUCUUCACUGUCAUUCUGAAAAUGUUUCAUUAUCAAACAUUUUGGUUAUCUUGUAUUUCCUAUAGACAAGGCAAGUAUUUUUAAUCUGAAGAUGCUGAGCCCCUUUAGAGUAUAAGCAGAAUAAUGUUUUUGUACAUAUGUGCAUUUUCUUUAAAGAUGGUUCAUAGCCUUCAUCACAUAUUCAAAGAGGACCGUGGCUCUUCUUUAGAUCUACAGUUUCAGAAUUUAAGAAGCACCUUCCCUUUUGCCACUUUUUCAAAUGAUUUCUUUUGACAGUACCUAUAUAAUAGGUAAUUUCUGGUUUUCUUUGAAUCUAUAUUUUCUAGAUAUCACCAGCUCAGUGUCAUAUGAAGGCCCUGAGUUGCAUUUUACAUAAGUCUUGUAAGUUCAGACUAAAUAAUGUAUUGAUUAUUGCCUUUCUUGUUCUUACACUUUUAUCAAUCCUUGGCACUUUAAUUAAAAUCUUAUCAUAAGGAACAAUUUCUCUUUUUCCUAGAAGUUUUCUUAUUCUCUAAGAAAUCAUGAGGUGUUUGGAUACCUGCCCUUAUUUCAAAGCAUGAUCUUUUUCUUGAAUUAGCAUCUGUUUCGAUAAUUUAAUUUUUUUGAAAGAGAUAUACUGUAUAUCCUUGUUUAUUAUACCAAGUCUGUCUCAUGGGGAUUUGUUUUUCAGAAUAGCCACUUUUGUUUAUGCCUUUCUUCUAGAAAUAGUCUUGCCUACUAAACAGUAUUGGUUUUCUUGGCAAAAUCUAUUCAAGAUUAAUUCUUUUCAGAAUGCAAAAUGGUGUUAUUUAUGUCAAACUGUGUUUUUAAAGUGAAAACUACAAAACCAUUGCAAUUAAACCUAGUGGAAAUGUCCUUGACAAAGUGAUUCUAAACUGAAAGAAUAAAACUUAGGAAGAUAGUUAAGGAAAUUUCGAAGGUAAAGAUUUAGGUGGCCAAUUAUUUAACAGUGUGACGGUGGUGGUGGUUAUGGGCAAAAUAACGUAAACAAAUAUUUAUUUAUUGGAAAGUGAAUUGGUGCAACCUUCAUGAAAGGCUGUUAGGUAAUUCAUAUGGAAAUCUUUUAAAAUGUGCAUUUCCAUUGGCCCAUCAUUUCAACUUUUAAGAAUUUUUAUAAGAAAAUAAUUGUGUGUAGCCAGGUGCAGUGGCUCACUCCUGUAAUCCCAGCACUUUGGGAGGCUGAGGCGGGCAGAUCACAAGGUCAAGAUAUCAAGACCAUCCUGGUCUACAUGGUAAAAACCCAUCUCUACUAAAAAUACAAAAGUUAGCUGCGUGUGGUGAUGCAUGCCUGUAGUCCCAGCUACUCAGGAGGCUGAGACAGGAGAAUGGCGUGAACCCGGGAGGCGGAGGUUGCAGUGAGCCAAGAUCAUGCCCCUGGACUCCAGUCUGGCAAUGGAGCAAGACUCCGUCUC